AUUCCCCGCACCCACCCACGUCUUCCCGGGAGUCGUAUCCCGAGCAUGGAGGUUACUGAGACCGUUAUUUCUUCAUGGCCUGCCUAGCUUAAGCAGUAGCUGGAAAAGAUGUCUCGGGCUGUUCGUCUUCCAGUCCCCUGUCCUGUUCAACUUGGUACCUUAAGAAAUGACUCCCUGGAAGCUCAGCUUCAUGAGUAUGUCAAACAAGGGAACUAUGUGAAAGUGAAGAAAAUUCUUAAGAAAGGAAUUUAUGUUGAUGCAGUUAACUCCUUGGGCCAAACAGCACUUUUUGUUGCGGCGUUAUUGGGCCUUAGGAAAUUCGUUGAUGUUCUGGUGGAUUAUGGAUCAGAUCCAAAUCACCGCUGCUUUGAUGGGAGCACCCCUGUCCAUGCAGCAGCAUUUUCGGGCAAUCAGUGGAUCCUUAGCAAACUGCUGGAUGCAGGAGGUGACCUGCGACUCCACGAUGAGAGGGGUCAAAACCCGAAGACUUGGGCUUUGACAGCAGGAAAGGAGCGUAGCACCCAGAUAGUGGAGUUCAUGCAGCGCUGUGCCUCACACAUGCAGGCCAUCAUCCAGGGCUUCUCUUACGACCUCCUGAAGAAGAUAGACUCCCCGCAGCGGCUUGUCUACAGCCCGUCCUGGUGUGGGGGCCUCGUGCAGGGAAACCCUAAUGGCUCUCCUAACCGACUGCUUAAAGCUGGAGUCAUUUCUGCUCAAAAUAUCUACAGCUUUGGUUUUGGGAAGGCUAUGCCUUGGUUUCAGUUUUAUCUUACUGGGGCGACACAGAUGGCCUAUCUAGGAUCUCUUCCGGUCAUUGGAGAAAAGGAAGUGAUUCAAGCUGAUGAUGAGCCCACCUUCUCUUUCUUCAGCGGCCCCUACAUGGUCAUGACCAACCUAGUGUGGAAUGGGAGCAGGGUCACAGUGAAAGAGCUGAAUCUCCCCACCCACCCACACUGCAGCAGGCUGCGGCUGGCCGACUUGUUAAUUGCCGAGCAGGAACACAGCAGCAAGCUGCGGCACCCCUACUUGCUACAGUUGAUGGCUGUGUGUCUCUCCCAGGACCUAGAGAAAACCCGCCUUGUGUACGAGCGCAUCACUAUCGGCACAUUGUUCAGUGUCCUUCAUGAACGACGGUCCCAGUUCCCAGUGCUGCACAUGGAGGUGAUUGUGCACCUGCUGCUCCAGAUAUCUGAUGCCCUGAGAUACCUGCAUUUCCAGGGGUUUAUCCACCGCUCCCUCAGCUCCUAUGCUGUCCAUAUCAUCUCCCCAGGUGAAGCGAGGCUGACCAACCUGGAGUACAUGUUGGAAAGCGAGGACAGAGGUGUACAGAGGGACCUGACUCGAGUGCCCCUUCCUACGCAGCUAUACAACUGGGCCGCACCAGAAGUGAUCUUACAGAAGGCAGCCACAGUGAAAUCAGACAUCUACAGCUUUUCUAUGAUCAUGCAGGAGAUUUUAACAGAUGACAUACCCUGGAAGGGCUUAGAUGGCUCAGUUGUUAAAAAAGCCGUAGUCUCGGGGAAUUAUUUAGAAGCUGAUGUCAGGCUUCCGAAACCUUACUAUGAUAUUGUUAAGUCAGGCAUCCACGUCAAGCAGAAAGACCGAACUAUGAACCUUCAAGAUAUCCGGUAUAUUCUGAAGAAUGACUUAAAGGAUUUUACUGGAGCCCAGAGAACUCAACCAACCGAGAGCCCCAGAGUGCAGAGAUACGGACUCCAUCCCGAUGUCAAUGUCUAUCUAGGACUGACUUCAGAACACCCCAGAGAGACACCUGACAUGGAAAUCAUAGAACUAAAGGAAAUGGGCAGUCAACCUCAUUCACCAAGGGUUCACUCUUUAUUCACUGAGGGGACACUAGAUCCUCAGGCCCCAGAUCCAUGUCUGAUGGCCAGGGAGACUCAGAAUCAAGAUGCUCCUUGCCCUGCUCCAUUUAUGGCAGAAGAGGCCAGCAGCCCCAGCACAGGUCAGCCAAGCCUCUGCAGUUUCGAAAUCAACGAGAUCUACUCAGGCUGCUUGAUUUUGGAAGAUGACAUAGAAGAGCCUCCAGGAGCUGCUUCAUCUUUGGAGGCAGACGGACCUAACCAGGUAGAUGAACUGAAAUCCAUGGAAGAAGAGCUGGAUAAGAUGGAGAGAGAGGCGUGUUGUUUUGGCAGUGAGGAUGAGAGCUCUUCAAAAGCUGAGACAGAGUACUCUUUUGAUGACUGGGACUGGCAAAACGGUUCACUCAGUUCACUCAGCCUUCCUGAGUCAACCAGAGAAGCCAAGAGCAAUUUGAACAACAUGUCCACGACUGAGGAGUAUCUCAUCAGUAAGUGUGUGCUGGAUCUAAAGAUUAUGCAGACAAUAAUGCACGAGAAUGAUGAUAGGCUGAGGAAUAUCGAGCAGAUAUUAGAUGAAGUCGAGAUGAAACAGAAGGAACAGGAAGAGCGCAUGUCUUUAUGGGCCACUUCAAGAGAGUUUACAAAUGCCUACAAGUUACCUCUGGCCGUGGGCCCUCCAUCUUUAAACUAUAUUCCUCCUGUCCUACAGCUUUCAGGGGGUCAGAAGCCAGACACCAGUGGCAACUACCCAACCCUACCAAGAUUUCCAAGAAUGCUGCCGACUCUUUGUGACCCUGGAAAACAGAACACAGAUGAACAAUUUCAGUGCACUCAAGGAGCCAAGGACAGUUUGGAAACAAGCAGGAUCCAAAAUACCAGUAGCCAGGGAAGACCUAGAGAGUCCACUGCCCAAGCCAAAGCCACACAGUUUAAUAGUGCACUCUUCACUCUGUCAAGCCACCGGCAGGGACCUUCUGCAUCACCCAGCUGUCACUGGGACUCUACCAGGAUGAGUGUGGAACCUGUUUCUUCUGAAAUCUAUAAUGCAGAGUCCAGAAAUAAAGAUGAUGGAAAGGUACACUUAAAAUGGAAAAUGGAGGUGAAAGAAAUGGCAAAGAAAGCAGCUACUGGACAGCUCACAGUACCUCCUUGGCAUCCUCAGAGUAGUCUGACUUUAGAGAGCGAGGCUGAAAAUGAGCCCGACGCCCUGCUGCAGCCCCCCAUUAGGAGCCCAGAAAACACGGAUUGGCAGCGAGUUAUUGAGUAUCAUAGGGAAAAUGAUGAGCCCAGAGGAAAUGGCAAGUUUGACAAGACGGGCAACAAUGACUGUGACAGUGACCAGCAUGGCAGACAGCCCAGGCUUGGAAGCUUCACCAGUAUCAGGCACCCAUCUCCCAGACAAAAGGAGCAACCAGAGCAUAGUGAAGCCUUCCAAGCAAGUUCUGACACAUUGGUGGCUGUAGAGAAAUCUUACAGUCAUCAGUCCAUGCAAUCAACUUGUUCACCAGAGUCUUCUGAGGAUAUAACAGAUGAAUUUUUAACUCCAGACGGUGAAUAUUUUUACUCCUCGACUGCUCAAGAAAACUUAGCUCUAGAGACCUCGAGUCCCAUAGAAGAGGACUUUGAAGGAAUACAAGGUGCAUUUGCCCAACCUCAAGUCUCUGGUGAGGAAAAGUUCCAAAUGAGAAAAAUUCUUGGAAAGAAUGCUGAGAUUUUGCCCAGGUCUCAAUUUCAACCUGUACGAAGUACUGAAGAUGAACAAGAAGAGACAUCAAAGGAGUCACCAAAGGAACUGAAAGAGAAAGACAUAUCAUUGACGGAUAUUCAAGACCUGUCUAGUAUCUCCUAUGAACCAGACAGCUCUUUUAAGGAAGCUUCAUGCAAAACACCCAAAAUAAACCAUGCACCUACCAGUGUCAGCACUCCACUCAGCCCAGGGUCCGUUUCUUCAGCUGCCAGUCAGUAUAAAGACUGCCUUGAAAGUAUCACAUUUCAGGUUAAGACAGAGUUUGCCUCUUGCUGGAACAGUCAAGAAUUUAUUCAAACUUUGUCUGAUGACUUUAUAAGUGUCCGAGAGAGAGCAAAGAAACUGGAUUCUCUCCUUACUUCCUCUGAAACUCCCCCUUCAAGACUGACUGGUCUUAAAAGAUUGUCUUCAUUUAUUGGGGCUGGAUCCCCCAGCCUUGUUAAGGCAUGUGACUCAUCACCACCCCAUGCCACCCAGAGAAGGAGCCUGCCUAAAGUAGAAGCCUUCUCACAGCAUCACAUUGAUGAGCUGCCACCACCAUCUCAGGAGCUACUUGAUGACAUUGAGCUCUUGAAACAGCAGCAGGGCUCAUCCACGGUGUUGCAUGAGAACACAGCAAGUGAUGGAGGAGGCACUGCAAAUGAUCAAAGGCACUUAGAAGAACAAGAAACUGACAGUAAAAAAGAAGAUAGUAGUAUGCUUUUGUCCAAAGAAACUGAAGAUCUUGGAGAGGACACAGAGAGAGCUCACUCUACUCUGGAUGAGGACCUGGAAAGAUGGCUGCAGCCACCUGAGGAGAGCGUGGAGCUACAAGACCUUCCCAAGGGCUCUGAAAGGGAGACAAAUAUCAAAGAUCAAAAAGUUGGUGAAGAGAAAAGAAAAAGGGAAGAUAGCAUUACACCAGAAAGAAGGAAAUCAGAGGGUGUUCUAGGGACUUCUGAAGAAGAUGAACUAAAAUCCUGUUUUUGGAAGCGACUAGGUUGGUCCGAAUCAUCCAGGAUAAUCGUGCUGGAUCAGAGUGACUUGUCAGACUGAUUGGAAUUGGAUCAUAGACGGACUCCUGGCCUGAGUUUGAGUGUCCUGGUUGUAAGCUCCUUUCUUCUCUUUCUGCUUCAGUUGCUGUCAGGGCAGCAGUUCCAGUUCUGUAAGUCUCACUUUGUUCAGCUGCCACAAUAGACAUCAUCGUUUGGCCCUCUCUGUUAGCAGCACAUUCAACCAUUUGUUUUCAGUCAGAUUUCUGAAAAGUGAGAGGUAGUUUUGAUAGUAAAAAUUUUUGGUUGUGCCUAGAAUGGCUUUGGUUUUGUUGAUGUUAAUUUUCAAAAACUUUAACUCUUGUUAUAUAAUAAAAUGUUUAAUUUUAAUAACAGA